AGAGCCAGCCCCACGAGGCCACGGAAGACAGGGUCACUUGUUCCUGCCAAGGAAAGAGGGUGGAAAAGUCAUUCAACUCAAGCAGAUCAAAGUUGUUUUGAGGCAGUAGGCAGACCCAGGACACCAAUGAACUGGACAUUUUUGAAAAUGUGCCAGCUUCUUUUGCUUAUAAGCACAAGGCCAUUGGUGUUCCUCAGCUGACUGGUGGUAAGAUUGGUACUUCAGGGGUACUGCUGCUACUACUAGAAAGCCCUACUUUGCAACACCAUGCAUUAGCCCAGAUCUAAAGGAAGAAGUUCUUGCUGCCAGGAUCCUCAGAUGCCCAUGAAGGGGCUUUCCAGGUGAUGGGGAGGGGCUUCAGGAUGUUCACCAUGACAAGAGCCAUGGAAGAGGCUCUUUUUCAGCACUUCAUGCACCAGAAGCUGGGGAUCGCCUAUGCCAUACACAAGCCAUUUCCCUUCUUUGAAGGCCUCCUAGACAACUCCAUCAUCACUAAGAGAAUGUACAUGGAAUCUCUGGAAGCCUGUAGAAAUUUGAUCCCUGUAUCCAGAGUGGUGCACAACAUUCUCACCCAACUGGAGAGGACUUUUAACCUGUCUCUUCUGGUGACAUUGUUCAGUCAAAUUAACCUGCGUGAAUAUCCCAAUCUGGUGACGAUUUACAGAAGCUUCAAACGUGUUGGUGCUUCCUAUGAAUGGCAGAGCAGAGACACACCAAUCCUACUUGAAGCCCCAACUGGCCUAGCAGAAGGAAGCUCCCUCCAUACCCCACUGGCGCUGCCCCCACCACAACCCCCUCAACCAAGCUGUUCACCCUGUGCGCCAAGAGUCAGUGAGCCUGGAACAUCCUCCCAGCAAAGCGAUGAGAUCCUGAGUGAGUCGCCCAGCCCAUCUGACCCUGUCCUGCCUCUCCCUGCACUCAUCCAGGAAGGAAGAAGCACUUCAGUGACCAAUGACAAGUUAACAUCCAAAAUGAAUGCGGAAGAAGACUCAGAAGAGAUGCCCAGCCUCCUCACUAGCACUGUGCAAGUGGCCAGUGACAACCUGAUCCCCCAAAUAAGAGAUAAAGAAGACCCUCAAGAGAUGCCCCACUCUCCCUUGGGCUCUAUGCCAGAGAUAAGAGAUAAUUCUCCAGAACCAAAUGACCCAGAAGAGCCCCAGGAGGUGUCCAGCACACCUUCAGACAAGAAAGGAAAGAAAAGAAAAAGAUGUAUCUGGUCAACUCCAAAAAGGAGACAUAAGAAAAAAAGCCUCCCAGGAGGGACAGCCUCAUCUAGACACGGAAUCCAAAAGAAGCUCAAAAGGGUGGAUCAGGUUCCUCAAAAGAAAGAUGACUCAACUUGUAACUCCACGGUAGAGACAAGGGCCCAAAAGGCGAGAACUGAAUGUGCCCGAAAGUCGAGAUCAGAGGAGAUCAUUGAUGGCACUUCAGAAAUGAAUGAAGGAAAGAGGUCCCAGAAGACGCCUAGUACACCACGAAGGGUCACACAAGGGGCAGCCUCACCUGGGCAUGGCAUCCAAGAGAAGCUCCAAGUGGUGGAUAAGGUGACUCAAAGGAAAGACGACUCAACCUGGAACUCAGAGGUCAUGAUGAGGGUCCAAAAGGCAAGAACUAAAUGUGCCCGAAAGUCCAGAUUGAAAGAAAAGAAAAAGGAGAAAGAUAUCUGUUCAAGCUCAAAAAGGAGAUUUCAGAAAAAUAUUCACCGAAGAGGAAAACCCAAAAGUGACACUGUGGAUUUUCACUGUUCUAAGCUCCCCGUGACCUGUGGUGAGGCGAAAGGGAUUUUAUAUAAGAAGAAAAUGAAACACGGAUCCUCAGUGAAGUGCAUUCGGAAUGAGGAUGGAACUUGGUUAACACCAAAUGAAUUUGAAGUCGAAGGAAAAGGAAGGAACGCAAAGAACUGGAAACGGAAUAUACGUUGUGAAGGAAUGACCCUAGGAGAGCUGCUGAAGCGGAAAAACUCGGAUGAAUGCGAGGUGUGCUGUCAAGGGGGACAACUUCUCUGCUGCGGUACUUGUCCACGAGUCUUCCAUGAGGACUGUCACAUCCCCCCUGUGGAAGCCAAGAGGAUGCUGUGGAGUUGCACCUUCUGCAGGAUGAAGAGGUCUUCAGGAAGCCAACAGUGCCAUCAUGUAUCUAAGACCCUGGAGAGGCAGAUGCAGCCUCAGGACCAGCUGGUGCUGCAGUUUGCUCAGGAAGCUGGAGAACAGAAGAGAAGGGCAGCGUGGCAGCAGUGGAGCGGGGCAGCAGGGAUUUUGCUGCACACUCUGGAGAGGGACUACCUGGUUCAAACUCCACCCCACUGCUCACGGGCUCUGGGAUACCGGAUUCGAGAUUACGGUGAGCCCUUUCAGGAAGCAAUGUGGUUGGACCUGGUUAAGGAAAGGCUGAUUACGGAAAUGUACACGGUGGCAUGGUUUGUGCGAGACAUGCGCCUGAUGUUUCGCAACCAUAAAACAUUUUACAAGGCUUCUGACUUUGGCCAGGUAGGACUUGACUUAGAGGCAGAAUUUGAAAAAGAUCUCAAAGACGUGCUCGGUUUUCAUGAAGCCAAUGACGGCGGUUUCUGGACUCUUCCUUGACCCUGUUCUGUAAAGACUGAAGCAUCCCCACCUCAGGAUUCAGCUGAUGGGACCCUGGCUUGGACUGUUGAUUGCCAGUGAGUCUGGGAUGUAAUUGGCUGCCCUCAGGACCCAAACCCAGACACUUCAUAGGAUUAUCACACCCUCCAUCUUUAUUCUUUCUUUUUACCUUUAAAAGUCUAUAUCUACACUAAAAAAAAAAAAAAUUAAUACUUCCUUAAUACCAUCAGAUACCCCAUCAUAGUUCACAUUCUCCCCACUGUCUCAUAAGUCUUUUUAGAGUUGAUUUGUUCAAAUCAGGAUCUAAACAAGUUCCACACACUGCAUUUGGCUCUCCUGUCCCUAUGUCUCUUUUAAGCUAUAAAUUGUCAUGUAUUUAUUGAAGAACUCAGGGUUUUGGUCCUAUUACAUUUUUUGCAAUCUGGAAUUUUCUGGUUGCAUUUUCUUAGUGGUAUAGUCCUCUCUUCCUCUCAUUUUUUGUAAGCUAGAAGUUAGAUCUAGAAGCUUGCUUUAACUCAGGUUUUGAGGGGUUUGUUUUGAUUUGGGGGUUUUGGGGCACAUGCAGGCUUCACAGGGGAAUUUAGUAUUAUUUUUUAUGUUAAGGUUGGCAGCAGGUGCACGUGUUAUCAGCCUGAUCAUCUAUCACCUGAUGGUUUUAGCAAUACCUAAAUCCGUGAUAUCAUCAGAGGUUGCAAAAUGAUGAGAUUCAGGUUUUUUUUUACAUAAUUAUUGGUCAGAAUUAUUCUGCAAAUAGCUUCUCUUUAACAGUAUUCGGUUACCUUGAAAUACAGGUUGUACAAAAAAUAGGAUAAAUGCUUGUUUUUUUAUUUAGCAAUGUUCAAAAUAAUGAAUUGAUGUCCCAAUAUCCUCUAAAGGUAACCAGGGAUUUUUUAAUUUAAUUAUCUUGAACCCACAUAUUUAAAUAUACGUAGCAUGCUACAAACCAUUGCAGUUAAUACCUUUAUUGAUGCUUGAGUUGCCCACUUUUUCUUUUUUUUUUUUUUUUUUUUUUUUUGAGACAGAGUCUCACUCUGUCACCCAGGCCGGAGUACAGUAGCGUCAUCUUGACUCACUGCAACCUCCUCCUCCUGGGUGCAAGCGAUUCUCCUGCCUCAGCCUCCGAGUAGCUGGGAUUACAGGCAUGUGCAAGUUCCCCACUUUUAGUGAGAAACUCCUCAAUUUGCCUCCUGAGUUGUUUUGAAAUGACCCCAGAACUCUUUGAUGGUGUAUUAGCUAUCUAUUGCUGUGUAACAAAUGACCUCAAAGCUUAGCUGCUUAAAAAGAAAAAAACAUUUUAUUGCUCACUAUUCUGUGGAUCAAGAAUUCAGGCAUCAUCCAUGAGGAUGCUUCCCUUUGCUCCACAUGGUACUGGCAGACCCCAUUCAUACUUGCACACUGUCACUUCUGCCACAAUCUAUUGGUGAAAGCAAGUCACAGGGACAGAUUCAGAAGGAGGGAGAAUAGACCUUACCUCUUGAUGCGAUGGGUGGCAAAGUCACAUUUCAAAGGAGAAUGUUGCUUGGGAAGAAACAUUGCUGCUCCCAUCUUUAGAAGCAAUCUACCAUAGUUCACCCUCUGGCCACAGUAGUUCACAUCUUUCCCAAAUGCAAAGGACACUCCUCUCCCCACAGAAGUCUCACUCUCUGCAGCAUUGGAACAAAGUCCAGGACCUCCUUAUCUAAAUCAGGUUCAGAUCAGAUAAAGCUUCUUCGGGCUGGGCACAGUGGCUCACACCUGAAAUCCCAGCACUUUAGGAGGCCGAGGCAGGUGGAUCGCUUGAGUCCAGGAGUUGAAGACCAGCCUGGGUAACAUGGCAAAACCUCAUCUCUACAAAAAAAAAAAAAAAAAAAUCUUUUUAAUUAGCUGGGCAAGGUGGCACACACCUGUAGUCCCAGCUACUCAGGAGGCUGAGGUGGAAGGAUGAGCCUGGGAGGCAGAGGUCGCAGUGAGCCAAGAAUGCACCACUGCACUCCAGCCUGGACAACAGAGACCCUGCCUCAAAAAAAAAAAAAAAAAAAGGAAAGAAAACAAAAGAAAUAGGCUCCUCAGGUAUGGUUUAUUGGGUGCAGCUCCUUGGGUGCACCUCCUCUUGAACUAGAGGCCUGUGAGCUGAAAAAUUGUUUCUUCCCUGCUGCCAACAGUCAGUGAUGAAACAGGGACUGAACAACUACUAUAGACACUUCCAUUCAAACGGGGAAAAAGGAAGCAGCAGUCACUCAUUUAUAGCAAUUCUGAAAUCCAGUCAAGCACAUGUUGCUAGUUCCCCCUAAUCCCAGGGCAGGAAAUUUUCCUUGAUACAUGAUUUAUAUGUAUGAUACACCUCUAAUUCCCAUCCCAUCCCAUCCUACCCCACAGGCUUCUUCCUUGUCUUCCUCGGUUCUGUAUUGGUGUCUCCCUUCUCCAACAGUAUUAUUUACUCACUUGCUCAAUCCCCAGGUACAACAAUAAAAGUUAACAGAAUUUUAACACUCAGAUCACUAUGAAAAACAAACUAAGUUGAUUUCUAAAUUUCUGUGGAGUUUAUUUUUGUUUGUUAUAGAUUUAAUAUACCAUUGCAGAGGGUAUUUAAUGUACCAUUGCAGAGGGUAUUUAAUAUACCAUUGCAGAGGAUUUUACAUUUGUAUUUAUAAAUGAGAUUGCUCUAUAGUUUUUACACACUGUCAUAGUCAGAUUUACGGUUAUCCUACCUCGGUAAAAUAACUUGUAAAAUUUUCUACCUUUUAAUAUAUUCUGGAAUAAUUUAUAGUGUUUUAAAUUAACCAAAAGUGUGUGACCCAGAGUUCACUGGAGAGACAGUGGUAACCACAUUAUCUGCUUUCUUUACGGUUUUCAGGCUAUGAAGAUAUUCUGUUGGUUUUUGAGACAGCUCUGCUUUUAUGUUUUUCUAAGAAGUCAUCUAUUUCAUUUGUGGUUAAAAGUAAUAUAGGUGGUCUGCCAGGCGCAGUGGCUCAGGCCUGUAAUCCCAGCACUUUGGGAGGCUGAGGCGAGUGGAUCGCGAGGUCAAGAGAUCGAGACCAGCCUGACCAACGUGGUGAAACCCCGUCUCUACUAAAAAUACAAAAAUUAGCCAGGCGUGGUGGCGGGCGCCUGUAGUCCCAGCUACUCAAGAGGCUGAGGCAGGAGAAUCGCUUGAACCCGGGAGGUGGAGGUUGCAGUGAGCCGAGAUCCCACCACUGCACUCCAGCCUGGGCAACAGAGUAAGACUCUGUUUCAAAAAAAAAAAAAAAAGUUAUAUAGGUGGUCUUAUUUCUGUCAUAUUUUAAUAUUUCUCUUUUUAAUGUUUUAAUGUUAUUUUUGUCUAUUUUUUUUCUUCUGCCUUCUAUUUUGGAAGGCAUCGUAACGGCUUUUAGUUCCAAUAUUUACCCAUAAGUUUUCCCAAUGCAUUUUGACUUAUUUUUUUAAUGUCAAAGUCAAAAAUAAAAUAUCUGUAAUGUGUCACAUACUUAAGGCAAUGCGUUUAUCACUUUGAUACCUCUCAGCUCCCUUAUUCCUGUCUUUUCACUCUCUUGAAAUACAGACAUGAAUUAGUAUUAAUUUUUUUGCUUUUACUCUAUAAUGUUUAUUCUAUUCAAUUAUAUUAUGUCAUUAUUUGUUAGUUUCACAUUAUGUAAAUUAUUUGUCAUGUCCUAUGUCAUAUAAAGUAAUUCAAAAGCAAAAAUUAAAAGUGUGUGUUACGUGAUAACCUGUAUUUUUGAGAACAGUAUUAAUGUGUUUCUGUUUUCACUGUUUAAGAUUCCCUGCUGGUCUUUUCUUGACACGACUUCUCCAUACUUCCUUUUUGCUCUGCCUUUCAGUCAACUGAAGUGUGUCUUUAAGUAAUUUGAAAAGAAUUACAUGGAUGGUAUGUUUUCUGAUUCACCAUAUCUUAGAAUGUGUUCUAUUGUUUUCAUAAAUUAAUAACAUAAUAUAUAACUUAUCAUAACUUCUCACCUUCAAAA